UUUUUUUUUUUUUUUUUUUUUGUGGAGACAGGGCCUAUGUUGCCUUGCCUGGUCUCAAGCUAUCCUCCCUGUUGGCCUCCCCAGGCUUUGAGAUUAUAGGCAUGGGCCGCUGCACCUGGCCUUAAUCUCAGCUAAUUGUUGGGGAAGGCAAAUAUAUAUUAUUGAUCUUGCUUUCCUUCCUGAGAAAUUCACGUCUCCUGGCUCUACAACAGUCAACAGUAUGGUCUGGUCUUCAUCCUGCCUCUGUGACUGCUCAUCAUCUUUCAUGGCUCUGUUUUCUUUGCAUAUCUUUUAGAUGUUGGCUUUGUCUUCUCUACUUAUUCUCUGGCCACUUUGAAUUCACUUUGAUUGCUUUAGUUGCCAUCCAUAAUAAAUAGAAAUCUUUAUUCUAGAUCUCUUUCCUGAGCUCCAGAUCCAUGUGUCCAGCUGACUACAGAAUAUCUCCAGUUGUAUGAUCUGAAGCCCCUAACUUUUUACCCCUUAACUUUGAUCCUUCUACAGGAUUUCUUAAAUUGGUAAAUGGCAUCAGCGUAUCAAUGAUUACCUCCACUCCCAUCCCCAAAUCCAGUCAGUCAGAAAAUGGAAUCAUCAAGACAGAUAAAGUAUUUGAAGUGAUGCUGGCUACAGACCGCUCCCACUAUGCAAAAUGUAACCCAUACAUGGAUUCUCCACAAUCAAUAGGUUUCCAAGCAACAAUCAGUGCUCCACACAUGCAUGCAUAUGCGCUAGAACUUCUAUUUGAUCAGUUGCAUGAAGGAGCUAAAGCUCUUGAUGUAGGAUCUGGAAGUGGAAUCCUUACUGCAUGUUUUGCACGUAUGGUUGGAUGUACUGGAAAAGUCAUAGGAAUUGAUCACAUUAAAGAGCUAGUAGAUGACUCAGUAAAUAAUGUCAGGAAGGACGAUCCAACACUUCUGUCUUCAGGGAGAGUACAGCUUGUUGUGGGGGAUGGAAGAAUGGGAUAUGCUGAAGAAGCCCCUUAUGAUGCCAUUCAUGUGGGAGCUGCAGCCCCUGUUGUACCCCAGGCGCUAAUAGAUCAGUUAAAGCCCGGAGGAAGAUUGAUAUUGCCUGUUGGUCCUGCAGGCGGAAACCAAAUGUUGGAGCAGUAUGACAAGCUACAAGAUGGCAGCAUCAAAAUGAAGCCUCUGAUGGGGGUGAUAUACGUGCCUUUAACAGAUAAAGAAAAGCAGUGGUCCAGGGAUGAAUUGUAAAAGCAACAUCAGCUUGACCAGUAUAAAAUUACAGUGGAUUGCUCAUCUCAGUCCUCAAAGCUUUUUGAAAACCAACACCAUCACAGCUUGUUUUGGACUUUGUUACACUGUUAUUUUCAGCAUGAAAAUGUGUGUUUUUUUAGGGUUUCUGAUUCUUCAAAGAGGCACAGAGCCAAAUUGGUAGAGGAAGGAUGCAAAGUAUAAAUUUGUGUAAUAUUACUUUAACAUGCCCAUAUUUUACUUGGAAAUAUUAAAAGAAAGGGUUCUGUAAAAUGGAAAACUUAGUUUGUGAAUUGAUUUUGAGGAGUGGUUUUUCUUUUCUUGGACACUUAAUUCUGUUCUGAUAUUAAUUUAUCAGAUUGCUUUUGUGCAUUGGAUAACACCACCAUUCACAAGUUAAGAUUCUUGGUAUUUGGAUAUCUGUUAGAUGCUACUAAGAAAAUAGAGAUGAGCUUUCUUUUUAAAGCUUUUGAUGUGGUGUCAUAGAAUAGCAUGUUGUAGAUACAAUCAGCUGCUUUGUUACCUUAAAACUAGGCAUUUGUAAAUAUUAAACCAUAAGAUGGCAGGUGAUGUCCUGUAAACACUCAGCUGUUCAGAUUGGACAUAACUGACUUAGUUCUUCCCUUCUCUCUCUCUCAAAAUUAUAGGAGACUUGUAGUUUAGUGUGGUUUUCUGUUUCUAAUUUGCUGCUGAUAAUGUAUAUGAACUUAACAUGCUGUGUAAGCUGUGUCCUAGUUCUUGAACAGUUUAUGCAGUGCUGCUUUGCCAAAUAAAGUUAAAAGUAAAAGAGGCA